AUGAAGGUGCUGAGGGCCUGGCUCCUGUGCCUGCUGAUGCUGGGCCUGGCCCUGCGGGGAGCUGCAAGUCGUACCCAUCGGCACUCCAUGGAGAUCCGCACCCCUGACAUCAAUCCUGCCUGGUACGCCAGUCGCGGGAUCAGGCCUGUGGGCCGCUUCGGUCGGAGGAGGGCAACCCUGGGGGACGUCCCCAAGCCUGGCCUGCGACCCCGGCUGACCUGCUUCCCCCUGGAAGGCGGUGCUAUGUCGUCCCAGGAUGGCUGA